GAACCUCAUUCUCCUGGGAACCCACCCAGAACCUCCACCCUCUGACGCCAUGGUCAGCUCCUGCUGUGGCUCUGUCUGCUCUGACCAGAGCUGUGGUCAAGGUCUCGGCCAGGAGAGCUGCUGCCGCCCCAGCUGCUGCCAGACCACCUGCUGCAGGACCACCUGCUGCCGCCCCAGCUGCUGCAUUUCCAGUUGCUGCAGGCCUUCCUGCUGUAUCUCCAGCUGCUGCAAACCCAGCUGCUGCAGGACCACCUGCUGCCGCCCCAGCUGCUGCAUUUCCAGUUGCUGCAGGCCUUCCUGCUGUAUCUCCAGCUGCUGCAAACCCAGCUGCUGCAGGACCACCUGCUGCCGCCCCAGCUGCUGCAUUUCUAGUUGCUGCAGGCCUUCCUGCUGUAUCUCUAGCUGUUGCAAACCCAGCUGCUGCCAGACCACCUGCUGCCGCCCCAGCUGCUGUAUCUCCAGCUGCUACAGGCCCCAGUGCUGCCAGCCCUCCUGCUGCCGCCCGGCUUGCUGCAUUUCUAGUUGCUGUCAUCCCAGCUGCUGUGUGUCCAGCUGCCGCUGCCCUUUCAGCUGCCCGACCACCUGCUGUAGAACAACCUGCUUCCACCCCAUCUGCUGCGGCAGUUCUUGCUGCUGAGUGAAGCUGCUCUGGAUUUGUGCACCUUCUUGCUCUCAACCUUCAGUUCAGGCACAGAGUAUCUAUUCAGAGAACAUGUGGACUUCCUGAUGUCGUGAAAACAGAGGCAUGGACUGAUUUGGAAAAUAUUUUAUUAGUAUGUAUUCUCUUUUAUAGAAGUUUUUAUUCCUAUUGAAUCUGAAUUUACAGUCAAAUUCCACAUCACAUGUUUUAGAAUUCUUUAUUCUAAUUCAAUAUACAUAAAUCUUCAAAUGGUAUCCUUCUAGAUGUUUCUUCCUAAUGUUUUCUGUGGUAUCAAUUUUCAUGUGGAAUUGUUUGAUGUUCCUCAAUAAAACUUCAUAGUGUUCAAAAGCA